AGCUAGCAGUGCAUACAUGGAAGGGCGUGGGUGGGAGUUGUGAUUAGAAAGGUCAAUAAAAGCUUCUAAAGACCCACAGGAGAGACCCAAAGUCUUCAAGCCUGGAGUUCCUGCUUGGUUCUUCCUGAGGUCUGAACACCCUGCAAACUGAGCCCAGAUCUGAAUUCUUGUUGGGAGCCAUUUUGUGAAGAGACGAAGACUGAGCUGGUUUGGCUGCAUUUCUGGCCUCGAGCCGCAGUCAGCUUCUCCACGUAGAACCCGGCAGUAGGAGACUUAGAAUCGAAUCUCUUCUCCCUCCCGCCUCCUGUUUUUGGCUUUUUGAGAAACCUUAUCAUCCAACACAAUGGCCAGCAACGUUACCAACAAGAUGGAUCCUCACUCCAUGAACUCCCGUGUGUUCAUUGGGAAUCUCAACACUCUUGUUGUCAAGAAAUCGGAUGUGGAGGCGAUCUUUUCCAAGUAUGGCAAAAUUGCGGGCUGCUCUGUUCAUAAGGGCUUUGCCUUCGUUCAAUAUGAUAAGGAGAAAAAUGCCCGGGCUGCUGUAGCAGGAGAGGAUGGCAGAAUGAUUGCUAGCCAGGUUGUAGAUAUUAACCUGGCUGCAGAGCCAAAAGUGAACCGAGGAAACGCAGGUGUGAAACGAUCAGCAGCAGAGAUGUACGGCUCCUCUUUUGACUUGGACUAUAACUUGCAACGGGAUUAUUAUGGUGGGAUGUACAGUUUCCCAGCACGUGUACCUCCUCCUCCUCCCAUUGCUCUGGCUGUAGUGCCCUCGAAACGCCAGCGCAUAUCAGGAAACACCUCACGAAGGGGCAAAAGUGGCUUCAAUUCUAAGAGUGGAAAGCGGGGAUCUUCCAAGUCUGGAAAGCUGAAAGGAGAUGACCUUCAGGCCAUUAAGCAGGAGUUGACCCAGAUAAAACAGAAAGUGGAUUCUCUCCUGGAAAACCUGGAAAAAAUUGAAAAGGAACAUUGCAAGCAAGGAGUAGAGGUAAAGAAUGCUAAGUCUGAAGAGGAGCAGACCAGCAGCUCCUCGAAGAAGGAUAAGACUCACGUGAAGAUGGAGUCUGAGGGGGGUGCAGAUGACUCUGUUGAGGAGGGGGACCUACUGUGUGAUGAUGAUAAUGAAGAUCAGGGGGACAACCAGCUGGAGUUGAUCAAGGAUGAUGAAAAAGGGGCUGAGGAAGGAGAGGAUGACAGAGACAGGGCGAAUGGCCAGGAUGACUCUUAAGCACAUAGUGGGGUUGAGAAAUCUUAUCCCAUUGUUUCUUUACCUAGGUGCUUGUCUAACAUCAAAUUUUUCACCAGAUCCUCUCCCUUAGCAUCUUCAGCACAUGCUUACUGUUCUCCCCAUCCUUGUCCUUCCCACAUUCAUUAAUUCAUAUUGCCCUGCACCUAGUUCCAUUUUCACUUCCCUUGAUGCUCCUAGAAGUUUUCUUAAGUCUUACCCUGCAAUUUUUGCUUUUAAUUUAGAUACCUCCUUAUGACUUAACAGUAAAAAGGAUGUAUGGUUUUUAUCAACUGUCUCCAAAAUAAUCUCUUGUUAUGCAGGGAAUACAGUUCUUUUCAUUUAUACAUAAGUUCAAUAGUUGCUUCCCUAACUGCAAAGGCAAUCUCAUUGAGUUGAGUAGCUCCUGAAAGCAGCUUGGAGUUAGAAGUAUGUGUGUUACACCCCAUGUCAGUGUGCUGUGUGGGGCAGUUCAACAAAAAUCUAACAAUGUAUUUUUGUGAAUGAGAGUUGGCAUGUCAAAUGCAUCCUCAGAAAAAUAAUUAGUGUUAUACUCUUAAAAUGUGUUUUCUAAAGUUGAUACUGUGGGUUAUUUUUGUGAACAGCUCCAUGUUUGGGACCUUUUUUCCUCAAAAUAAACAAGUCCUUAUUAAACCAGGAAUUUAAAGAAAAAAA